AUGACCCAGAGGCAGGGGUCAGGGGGAGAGGUAGAGAUGAGACAAGAGGUAGAGGGGAGAGGUAGAGGUAGCCACGAGCUGAUAAUUACAGACAAGAGAUGCGGAGUAUGUGGGGGCUCAUUAUCCUGCAUAGUCUAUCUUUGUAUAUCUUUGAACUUUUCAAGAAUAAAAAAGCUUAAAAAGUAUACAUGGCCUGGUCCUACCAGAGACUCACCCAAUGCCAGCCUCCAGCCAGGGAGAGCCAAGUUUGCAUUUUCACACGCAUCUCACACUCCUCUGCACUCUCAACUUGGAGCGCUCCAAACAGGGAAACCCCAAGCCUUGCUGGCUUCUGCCAACCCCCUGAGCAGAAGCAUGGGUCCCCCUGAUCACCACCUCACCACCCUCAUCCUGAUCUCACUGGAGACUCCCUUUCCCGGUCUGCUAAGUAGCGGGUGUUUUUCCUUGACACUAACGCUACAGCUAGACCACGGUGGGCUUGGCAACAGGUGUCUUCCCAGAUGCUGGCGUUACCGCUAGACCAAGGAGCCCUCUGGUGGCCCUGUCCGGGCAUAACAGAAAGCUUGCACUCUUGUCUUCUGGUCACUCCUCACUGUCCCCUCAGCUCCCAUCUCUGUAU